UGCUCAGGUUUGUAGCCUAGGAGUGACAGGCUAUCCCAUUAUAGACUAGGUGUGUAGUAGACUAUCACAUCUCAGUUUGUGCAAGUGCACUCUAUGAUGGUCACACAACAACAAAAUUAUAUGACAAUGCAGUUCUCAGAGCGAAACCUUGCCUAAGAGAUACAUGACUAUACUUUUAAACAAGGUAAAGAAAAUACUGUGUGUAGAAAGGUCUUGCAGAAGGUUUGAACCACAGAAACUAAAGCAAGAUCUGCUUCUAUAAGGAGUCUAUUAAUGUAGUAUAUAUAAUGUAUUUUAAAAUAUGCCAGAAGAGCUCAGUGCCUAGAGCUGAGGAAAAAGACAGUGAAUUCGUAACAUCCUAUCUGGGUUAUUUUUUUCUUAUUAUUUAAACCUGCUCUUUGCAUUGCCCUCUUUCUCACCUCUCAGGUCAGGAGUCUUGUGUAUGGGAUCUGGCAACCCUUUCACUGAUACCUGGAAUAGCAUCUGAAUGCUGAGGCCUCCAGGGGGAAAGGCAGCCCCUGACCAGUGCUGCAGACCUAGUACUCACCUUUUGCUUAGCUUCACUAUCCUUCCAACCUGAGUGUGCCUUCAUCCAGUCCCCAAACUUAGAAAACAGUAAAGACCAGAAGAAUGGGCUUUUGCUCAGUCUGCUUAAUCAAAUUUUUAAAAUGAAAAACAUCUCAUUUGCCUCUAGUUAUGUAAAGAAGAAAGAAGCAGAGGGAGAGGAAAGCAGAUUUUCCUCGGUCCAUUUGUUCAACACAAAGAUAGUCUUUUAGUACCAGCCUGUGUCAUUCUCUUGGGAGUGGUAAAGAGGGGGUUUCAAUCUGGGCACUUUUAUUUGGAAAGAUAAUCUUUGACUUGCAUUUCUAAAAUACAGUCUGGGCCAAUAGGGACUGAUUCAUGUGGUCAUUGAAACCAGGUUCCAGAAGAAAGAAUUAUAACAAAAUGCUAUAAACCGCUUAGUAUGCCUCUAAUUUGUAAUAUUUACCGGAUAUGCUUUCCUGUUCCAAAAAAGGAAAAUUAAAUAUUAUUUCAGUUUUUCUGUGGCCCCUUGAUAACCCUCUAAAAUCUCUAAAGCUAGCCUUGAGAUGGUCUGGGCAGAGAGAUUUGUAGAAGUUGGGAAUGAGAGCUCUAUAGUACCUGGUUUCUGGGGAUAGAGGGUGGGUGGUGUCUGGCUUUGGUUCUUUGGAAAACCCUUCAGUUUACCCUGUGGGGACCAGGGCUCCCCAUCAAGCCGGACCUCAGACAUUGAGUCUGGCAGCAUAUUGUACUUCUAGUGUGUCUGAUUAACAUAGUUGAGCAAAACCUGUUUUACAGUUUGUAGCAAGAGAUGUUUGUAAUUGCCUGGUGGAUUUAACAGAGAUACAGCCAUCCUAUUUUAGGCCACUUUUGCCCUAUUUCUGGAUGUGGAGUCACAAUUUUCAUGAAUAAUACUAAACCUCUGCAUGAAGCCUGCUAUUCAUGAUUAGUAUUGAACUUGUCAUACAGAAAAAGUCCUGUGACAUGAUCAGAUUCCUGGAAAGUUCAUAUCUGAAUAUAACAGACCCAGCAGGAGCCAGGGGGAAUGAAUGUUUAGGGACAAAGCAGAAUCUGGCUGAAUGGUGGGCCAUUGUGUGGAAACCAGAUCUCUGCCCCUUGGUGUGUUAUGUGUAGAGCUACAACAAGCAGGAGGCAGACCUGAAGUACAACUCAAAUGGGAGCAGAGGGAAAUCUGAACUGCUCUUGACCUGCAGAGCAUGGAUCAGAACUUACUGUUAAAAGAACAACUCGGAGUGCCUGGAAACCUUGGCUGCUACAAGGAUCAUGGAAACCCACCUCCUCUAACUGGCACCAGUAAAACGUCCAACAAACUCACCAUACAAACUUGCAUCAGUUUUUGUCGGAGUCAGAGGUUCAAGUUUGCUGGGAUGGAGUCAGGCUAUGCUUGCUUCUGUGGAAACAAUCCUGAUUACUGGAAGUACGGGGAGGCAGCCAGUACCGAAUGCAACAGCGUCUGCUUCGGGGAUCACACCCAACCCUGUGGUGGCGAUGGCAGGAUCAUCCUCUUUGAUACUCUCGUGGGCGCCUGCGGUGGGAACUACUCAGCCAUGUCUUCUGUGGUCUAUUCCCCUGACUUCCCCGACACCUAUGCCACGGGGAGGGUCUGCUACUGGACCAUCCGGGUUCCGGGGGCCUCCCACAUCCACUUCAGCUUCCCCCUAUUUGACAUCAGGGACUCGGCGGACAUGGUGGAGCUUCUGGAUGGCUACACCCACCGUGUCCUAGCCCGCUUCCACGGGAGGAGCCGCCCACCUCUGUCCUUCAACGUCUCUCUGGACUUCGUCAUCUUGUAUUUCUUCUCUGAUCGCAUCAAUCAGGCCCAGGGAUUUGCUGUUUUAUACCAAGCCGUCAAGGAAGAACUGCCACAGGAGAGGCCCGCUGUCAACCAGACGGUGGCCGAGGUGAUCACGGAGCAGGCCAACCUCAGUGUCAGCGCUGCCCGGUCCUCCAAAGUCCUCUAUGUCAUCACCACCAGCCCCAGCCACCCACCUCAGACUGUCCCAGGUAGCAAUUCCUGGGCGCCACCCAUGGGGGCUGGAAGCCACAGAGUUGAAGGAUGGACAGUCUAUGGUCUGGCAACUCUCCUCAUCCUCACAGUCACAGCCAUUGUAGCAAAGAUACUUCUGCACGUCACAUUCAAAUCCCAUCGUGUUCCUGCUUCAGGGGACCUUAGGGAUUGUCAUCAACCAGGGACUUCGGGGGAAAUCUGGAGCAUUUUUUACAAGCCUUCCACUUCAAUUUCCAUCUUUAAGAAGAAACUCAAGGGUCAGAGUCAACAAGAUGACCGCAAUCCCCUUGUGAGUGACUAAAAACCCCACUGUGCCUAGGACUUGAGGUCCCUCUUUGAGCUCAAGGCUGCCGUGGUCAACCUCUCCUGUGGUUCUUCUCUGACAGACUCUUCCCCUCCUCUCCCUCUGCCUCGGCCUCUUCGGGGAAACCCUCCUCCUACAGACUAGGAAGAGGCACCCUGCUGCCAGGGCAGGCAGAGCCUGGAUUCCUCCUGCUUCAUCGAUUGCACUUAGGAGAGAGACUCAAAGCCCUGGGGCCCGGCCCUCUCUGCAUCUCUCUCUGAUCUAGCUAGCAGUGGGGGUGUCAGGACAGUGAGGCUGAGAUGACAGAGGUGGUCAUGGCUGGCACAGGGCUCAGGUACAUUCUAGAUGGCUGUCAGGUGGUGGGUAGCUUUAGUUACAUUGAAUUUUUCUUGCUUCUCUAUUUUUGUCCACACACAAAUCAGUUUCUCCUGAUCUUUAUGUCUUGGAACAGGGCCAGACAGGGAGAACUCUCAGGUACUCUUGGGAGUUGGUCCCAUACAAGUGCGGACUCCUGGACAUUAGCGAGGUGUAAAGAGGGCAGUGUCUGUGCUGCCCCGGCAGCUUUGCUCUCCAGAUGCUGGACUAGGGUGGGCCUCCUUCAGCCUGGGAGGGUCUGAGAAUAAGAUCUAGUGACCCCCAUUUAUAUCAAACCUGAUACCUUACACAUGGGCUUCUUUCUAGAUUCUUCUUUCCAUAGCUCAUGGAGCUGCAGGGAAAGCUUUAAGAGCUUUGGUCAUAUAAAACAUCCAUUCAGCUGGGCGCGAUGGCUCAUGCCUGUAAUCCCAGCACUGUGGGAGGCUGAGGCGGGCAGAUCACCUGAGGUCAGGAGUUCGAGACCAGCCUGGCCAACAUGGUGAAACCCCGUCUCUACUAAAAAUAUAAAAAUUAGUCAGGCGUGGUGGCAGGCGCCUGUAAUCCCAGCUACUCAGAAGGCUGAGACAGAAGAACAGCUUGAACCCAGGAGGCUGAGAUUGCAGUGAGCCGAGAUCGCACCACUGCACUCCAGCCUGGGUGACAAGAGUGAGACUCUGUCUCAAAAAAACAAAACACAAAUAAACAAAAAAAAUCCAUUCAUUUACUCAUGCAAUAAAUUCUCCUGCAAGCUUUUAUGGGCACUCAGUAAGUACUCAGGAUUGGCUUUAUCAGCCUUGCCACUGAGCAGCUCAUGGUCCUAUGGAACCUGAGCCAGGCCUCAGUCUCUCCAUGAUUGGCUCAGCUAACUCUCAGUUCAGAGUGGAGAGUAUCAAUCUUGUGUUUUUGCCCUUAGGCAGCACUAUAUGAGACAUGGGGCCUGUGGUCCUUCCUUCUGGUGUCCCCCGUGUUAAAAGAUAAAAAACACCCCAAGGGCCGGGCGCGGUGGCUCAUGCCUGUAAUCCCAGCACUUUGGGAGGCUGAGGCGGGUGGAUCACGAGGUCAGGUGAUCGAAACCAUCCUGGCUAAGAUGGUGAAACCCCGUCUCUACUAAAAAUACAAAAAAUUAGCUGGGUGUGGUGGUGGGCGCCUGUAGUCCCAGCUGCUCGGGAGGCUGAGGCAGGAGAAUGGCGUGAACCCGGGAGGCGGAGCUUGCAGUGAGCAGAGAUCACGCCACUGCACUCCAGCCUGGGUGACAGUGCAAGACUCUGUCUCAAAAAAAAAAAAAACACUCCAAGGGCCAUCCGUGCUCUCUGCCCCUCCUGUGGGGACCAAGUGGGGUUAGGAAUGGCUCAGUGGGGAAGGAGAGCACUCUUGUCCCCAGUCCCUUGCCACCCUGUCCCUUAGAUAGGGAGGUGGGCUGCAGAGAUUGGUGCCAGAAGAGGGUGGGUUUGGGAAUUGGAGCUCCUCCAAGGAGCUCCUCCUAAGAUUGAGUGCUGCAGCUGUAGUGGCUGCUGGUUGGGAGAGUAAGUGCCAUCACUAAUUUAAAAGUCCUUGCCAUCUGGAAUCAGGCUUUGUCAACAGCAGCUGAGAAAAGCAGCCUGUGCCUCUGCUGGCCAGGCCUAGGCCCUCGUCAGAGCGUGCCUCUCCACAAGGCACUUGGGCCUGGGUGAUUGUUGCGCCUCUGGCUUUGGCGUUUCCUCUUUGCAGCACUUUGCCUACCUCCCCCAAGCCCUGAGCCACUGCCUGCUGGGGCUCCUACUGAGGUUCUGGAAACACCUCUGCACCUGCCGCCCCUGGGAGGAAAGAGGGCCACACAGGAAGUGUCUGCAGGGAGAGGUGGCACUCGGCAGCCUGAGUUCAGGAGAGGUGCUUGGAGCUUCAGGCAGAGGGGCCUUCAGAGGAGGGAAACGGAGCAAUGUGUCACAGGCAGGCAGGGGCAGGACUGCCACCCCAGGCCCCGUGGGAGGCCUGCUGAGGGCACAGAGCUGCUCGGUGCAGCCUUCAUGCUUUGAUCUGGAAAGAGCAGCUGUCCGCAGGCCUCUGUCUCCAAGAGGCCUGUCACACAGGAGGACCGCUGGAAACAUACCAACACGUGCAGUCUCCCCUCCAAGCUAUUCAUGCUGUUUGUGGAAUCUCUCUCAAACAUAAGUGUCAGGUGUGUGUCGUCCCAACGGGUCCUGUGCUGUGAAUAGAUCCAUGUGCAGCACAAAGGGAAUGUGGCACGUGGCCCCAGGAAGAGUUCACCCGGCCAGGGGGCAGUUGUUCAGUUGCCUGGGGCUGACACUGACCACUGGCCUCUGGGGUGUCCUGCAGCCCAAAUGCCCACCUUGCCCUCCUCACAUCUCAGUCAGGGGAGGCCAUGCCCAAGCCAAUGUGCUGUCACAGCCUGCAGCGGGGGCAGCACUUCCUCGGAGGGCCUGGGAGGUGCUGGGGAUGCCCCAGCGCUUCUCUUCCUGCCUCGCCCUGGCAUGGCCCAGCGCCUCUAGGAUCAACUUACGAUCCGUGGAGCAGCCCCGGGAAACCCAAAUCUGGCUCAGGACAGCGUACGGGCAGGAGGGCUGUAAAUCAUCCCAGGCUAAGCCUCCGUGGGCACUGGCUCCUGCCGCAGCCUGGCUAUGGACUCAGUUAGAACCAGGUAGAAAGUCAGCGACACCCCACAGAAGGCCACUGCGGCUAGGUAAACACCUGAGAAAGAAACUGCUCCAGAAGAGAUGACGUGGGCUUCCAGGAGCAUGGAGGAGGUGGCACUUGAACUUUUAGGAAACUCCUUAGAUGAGAUAAAGUGGGGGUUGGAGGUGGCGAAAAGAGGGUAACCCUGGGAAAGUCAGUCAGAACCCAUGGCAGAAGACUGCAGGAGAGGCAGGGGAGGGGCUUCGGGGACCACUGUGGACAGAGCUCUGAAAGCACCCUGGCCAAAGCCCCUCCUGAGGUGACAGAGCGUGGGAGGAGGCUGCACUGGGCCUGCGUGCCAUCCUCACCCCUGUUCCCCGCUGGCGCCAGGCCCUGCCUUCUUGGUACCUGUGCCAACAGGAGAGCCCUCACCAGCCGAUCUUGUCACUCUCCGUGGUGACAGUGUCUUGGCCAGCUGUGGCCCCUAGUUUCUAGCAGCGUUUCUCAGUGUCCUUGGCCCUUCUGAGAAGGCAGGCGGGAGGCACACGGUGCCCUGUUCUUCCCCGUUUGUCCAGUUGCUUGCAAAGCAGAGAAUGAGUAGGAGUGAACCCGAGUGACUUCACCCGCCCUGUCCCCCACGUCAGGACAGGCUUGAGGCCUCUCUGGGCGUGAGCGAGGAAACCAGGCUGCUCUAACUUCUGAAGAGUGGGCUCUGGCUCAAGACUCCAAUCGGCCAGAAGCCCACAGAGAUCAAAGCACUAGCAAGUUCAGCUGUCCUGGCCCUCGGGUAGAACCCACGGGCGUGCCUGGGUGCGGCUCCACCCACAUGCCCCACUGUCAGCCCAGGCAGGAGCCUUCCUGGCCGGGCUCAGGAUCUGCCUGCAGCCCAGCCAGGCCAUCACCCAGCCCCGAUGCAUCCUGGCACUGCACGCUUACUCUUCACAAGCACUUAUACGCGGAUGGCCUCCGAGACCCUGCCUCCCUGGUCUGCUGAGGUCAGGCCAGGUCUCCCACGGAGCCGGGCAGCUCCACACCCCACCACCUGGCACCGUUAGGUUUCAGAUCUCCCGUGUGGUGUUUGAUGUCGGCUUUUGUUCCUACCUUGGGAGUUUGGAUUGUUUCCUCUGGUGUCUUUGUUUACCUUCCUCACUGUUCUACCUCCUGGCCAGGUCUCAGCUUAGCUUCCCUGGUGUGGGGUGUUUUUCAAGCCUUCCAGCCACAGCUGUCUCCCCUCAGGCUGGACGGCUCCGGGGUGACAGGGCUUCACCCUCUGCCUGCAGACCCCUGGUGGGCACAUCUCACAGGCUUCCGUCUUGCUGAGUUGGGUACGGAGGCAGAAGUGGGGUGUGGAGGAAAGUCAGAGGGAAAUCUGCUUCAGAAAGGAAGGGUCUUUAGACACAAAGACUGGAGGCCCUUCCCCGCCCGCACGGGAGCUGCCAUCGUGGGUCUCAUGCACGUCAAGACCUUCCCACAUCCAAACUCAGCUUCCAGCAGGGAUUUUGACUUUGGAUGACAAGGCUUUAUUUGUAAAUAUGCUCUUAAUAUGCAACUUUGAGAAUAAAAUAGAAACAUCAUGUAUUUUAAAAUAUAAGAUGAAGUGUGACGCACUGUAUACAAUUUAAUAUAUAUUUUUAGGGUUUUGUUAUUUAAGAAAAUGGAAUGUAAUGGUACUUUUACAAACGAGAAAAAAUGUUAUUUUUACUUUCUGGAAAAAAUAAAUAUUCUCAUUGUUGUAGAAAGA